GCUGCCGAAGAGGCCGGGACCAGGGUCCCCAGCUUGGGCCCGUGACGGCUUUUUCAUGCCCUAGUUGGGGUCUCCAGGGCCCGCGCGGGCAUUCUGGAAGGUUCUGCGUCCUUUAGGGUUGGAGGCCUGGGCCCGUAGGUGGGAGGACUGACGGGCUCCAGUCCUUCGGCAACACCAAUUCUGUCUGCACUCCCCAGGUCUGUCAGUCCCUCCCCCUCCUGUCAUUGUUCCCAGGACACCCGGGGCACUCCAGUCUUGUCAAGGCCCCUAAUUCUGUCAGUGCCCUCAGUCCUUUCAGUGCCUCCUAGGCCUGCCAAGACCCCUCAAUCCUUCUAGUAUACCCCCAGUCCUUCUGGGUCCCCCAAUCAUAUCAGUUUCUGGACUGCCAGGGUUCCCCAACCUUGGCACGGUUCUUCUAGUCCUAUAAGUGCCCCGGGCCUGCGAGCCCCGCGUUUUGUUAGUACCGCCCCCUAUUCCUGUUAGCCCGCCCUCUAGUCUAAUAUGGAUCGCCACUUCUGUCUGGGUCCCUGAUGUUGUUAGUGUGAGUAAAGGCCCUUGUUUUGCAAGGGUCUCUAAAUUGGUCAGGGCCCCUUUAACCUGUUAAGGUUGCUUGGUCCUGUUAAAGCCCUCCGUUCUUGUUAGGACUCCUCGAUUGCCUGGGUCCCCAAUCCUGUCAGGGCCCCCAUUUCCCUCUUAUUCACCCUCCCAAGGGCUCCAGGCUUCAGAACUGAGUACCCCCUCCCCCACUGCUGACCCCAAAUGACUGAGACCUGUUGCUCAGGUCGGCUUCCUCUGGAACUGGAGCAGGUUUAAAGAGCUUAUUAUCCCAGGGCUGAAAGUCCUCGAUACUUAUCCUGUCCAGUGCCCCCAUUCCGUAGAUAGGAAGUGUGGCCCCAUAGCUGACCUCAUAGCAGAGUUGGGAGGAGAAGCCAGAUCUUUUCAUCCGCAGGCCCCACCACUCUCCUCGUGAUGUCAUUUUGCAGAGGAAUGGAGUUUCCAAAGUCGCCACUUGUCCCUGGGUAUUUUUUCCUUAUGCUGCCAAAGUCAUGGACAAGUCCUCUCUCCCAUCCCCUUGACACUCUUCCCUUCAGUUUCCAUCUUGAACUUCGUGGUUUUAAGCACAGACCUGGGGAGACAGACAGGCAUGAUUCAGAGCCAUGUUCCUUCACUCACUGUGACCAAGUUGGGCUCUUAGUUUCUUCUGCUAUAAAAAUGAAAGUGAUAGUAGAACCUGCAUCUGUGGGGUUGUUUUAAAAAUGAGAUAUAAAGUCAUGAAGAACUGGGGAGUUAUAGGUGGAAUUGCUGCUGCUCUUGCAGCAGGAAUAUAUGUUAUUUGGGGUCCCAUUACAGAAAGAAAGAAGCGUAGAAAAGGGCUUGUGCCUGGCCUUGUUAAUUUAGGGAACACCUGCUUCAUGAACUCCCUGCUACAAGGCCUGUCUGCCUGUCCUGCUUUCAUCAGGUGGCUGGAAGAGUUCACCUCCCAGUACUCCAGGGAUCAGAAGGAGCCCCCCUCACACCAGUAUUUAUCCUUAACACUCUUGCACCUUCUGAAAGCCUUGUCCUGCCAAGAAGUUACUGAUGAUGAGGUCUUAGAUGCAAGCUGCUUGUUGGAUGUCUUAAGAAUGUACAGAUGGCAGAUCUCAUCAUUUGAAGAACAGGAUGCUCACGAAUUAUUCCAUGUCAUUACCUCGUCAUUGGAAGAUGAGCGAGACCGCCAGCCUCGGGUCACACAUUUGUUUGAUGUGCAUUCCCUGGAGCAGCAGUCAGAAAUAACUCCCAAACAAAUUACCUGCCGCACAAGAGGGUCACCUCACCCUACAUCCAAUCACUGGAAGUCUCAACAUCCUUUUCAUGGAAGACUCACUAGUAAUAUGGUCUGCAAACACUGUGAACACCAGAGUCCUGUUCGAUUUGAUACCUUUGAUAGCCUUUCACUAAGUAUUCCAGCCGCCACAUGGGGUCACCCAUUGACCCUGGACCACUGCCUUCACCACUUCAUCUCAUCAGAAUCAGUGCGGGAUGUUGUGUGUGACAACUGUACAAAGAUUGAAGCCAAGGGAACGUUGAACGGGGAAAAGGUGGAACACCAGAGGACCACUUUUGUUAAACAGUUAAAACUAGGGAAGCUCCCUCAGUGUCUCUGCAUCCACCUACAGCGGCUGAGCUGGUCCAGCCACGGCACGCCUCUGAAGCGGCAUGAGCACGUGCAGUUCAAUGAGUUCCUGAUGAUGGACAUUUACAAGUACCACCUCCUUGGACAUAAACCUAGUCAACACAACCCUAAACUGAACAAGAACCCAGGGCCUACACUGGAGCUGCAGGAUGGGCCGGGAGCCCCCACACCAGUUCUGAAUCAGCCAGGGGCCCCCAAAACACAGAUUUUUAUGAAUGGCGCCUGCUCCCCAUCUUUAUUGCCAACGCUGUCAGCGCCGAUGCCCUUCCCUCUCCCAGUUGUUCCCGACUACAGCUCCUCCACAUACCUCUUCCGGCUGAUGGCAGUUGUCGUCCACCAUGGAGACAUGCACUCUGGACACUUUGUCACUUACCGACGGUCCCCACCUUCUGCCAGGAACCCUCUCUCAACUAGCAAUCAGUGGCUGUGGGUCUCCGAUGACACUGUCCGCAAGGCCAGCCUGCAGGAGGUCCUGUCCUCCAGCGCCUACCUGCUGUUCUACGAGCGCGUCCUUUCCAGGAUGCAGCACCAGAGCCAGGAGUGCAAGUCUGAAGAAUGACUGUGCCCUCCUGCAAGGCUAGAGCUGAUGGCACUGUCUGCACUGUCCAGGAAAAAAGUAAAACUGUACUGUUGCGUGUGCAAGCGGCCCCACUAGAGCCUUCCAGCCUUCUGGUGUGUUCUAAGAGCAGGCUCCACCUGGGAGCCAGCCCCAGUUCACACCAAACCAGGCUCCCUGAACAGUCCUGUUCAUGUGUGUAGGUGGUUCUGUUGUGUUAAGAAAGCAUUCAUUAUGUCCGGAGUGUCUUUUUACUCAUCUGAUACAGGUAAUUAAAAGAACUCAGAUUCUUGAAGCCACCGUUUUCAUAUUGUAAUGUUAGGUGUUCUCAGAGGGGAGGUACCUUUGUCUAAUCAACGUUUCCACUUAGAUCUUUUAUUUUUAAUAAGCAGGCCCAUAAAAAUUGUUGACAAGAAUUAAUGAAAUUAUUAAAGGCAACAAUUUAGAAGAAAAAGUGCCUUUCACUUUCGAUUGCUUUUGUAGCACGUCCAUUGUGAAAUAUUCCUUCCAGGCUACUCAAAGGAUAGCAAGAGAACAGGUAAAUGAUGCCUAAAGAACACCUUCCUUUUUCUAUGCCUUUUCUAAUCUUUCAAUUCUUUCUAUGGAGUAAAGGCUCAUCUGCCAAAUCUGCCCCCUGGGGAAACUCUUUCACUACUUUGUCAGUUAUAAGUGAAGAGCUUACUUGUUGCUUUUAUCUUUUGUAUAUUGGACUGAGAUGUAAUUACACUGUAUUAUAAAACUCUGUGAAUAGCCAGAACUGAGCUGGAUCUUUGCAACACCUGAUUCCUCUGCUCUGUGGAAAACUUUUUCUUACACAAGGAUCCACUGUGGACGGUUACUUUCAUCUGUUUAUUUAUUGCCCAUGCAGAGCUCUUAAGGUUUACAGGUGGGAGCUUGGGGCUGUAUAAAAAAAUAAUCCCUGCCCUGAGUUGACACCUGGCUUAGGAAGGAAGGGCUGACUAUGGGGCUGCAGUCUCUCUGAACCUCAGUUUCCUCAUUUGUGAAGUGAAGGGUUAGAUUUGAUGACCACCAAAGUUCAGCCCUUUUCACGAAAAGGAGAAAGCAGCUUUUGACUUUUUAAAAAACAUAUAACUACAGCUGGCAUCUAGUAUUGUCAUGUUGCUCUAGGUCCAUAUUCUGAAUUUAUUCAUUUCCAAUAGCCUAAUACAAAAAGUAUAUAUUGAGCACUUUCUUCCCUUUUCAGGUAAGUCUCUGAAUGCAGCCCAGGGCCAAAGGAAUUUUGAUGACACAGUAGUACCUAUGUUUUAAGCUAUAUUUUUAAUUUAGAAAAAUGGAUACCAAAUUCAAACCGACUCAUCAGAGGUAAGAUUUGGAAUCAGACCUUUCCAAAAGGUCAUCUGAGGUAAGGCUAAGACCGCACUUCCUCUGCUGGGGGUGAGCUGGCAGACACACCAAACAGUGCCUUGGCAGCAGCUCACAGUGCAGGAAGCCCAGGUGAUCACUCUUCUGCUGGGCCCAGGCUGCACCCUGAGGACUCAGUAACUCACUCUCAACAGAAUAUUCUGUGCAGGCUCUCCAGGCUCUGGGCGUCAGGGUGCAAGGGGCAGCUUGAACUGUACGGUCCGUCCUGCACUCACCCGAUGCAGACCUUGACUUUGAUGUUGAAAUGAACACACUUGUUUUACCCAAGUCUGGUGGAACAAAUGCCCAAUCAUGUGACCUUAAAGUGUACUGCAAAGCUGUAGCUUUAAGUAAUUGCUGUUCUGCCACUGCUUACUCUGAAAUCUACCAUCAAAGAAAGAUAGAGAAAAGGGGCUGAGCCUUGGAAUAUAUGGUUAUAAGCAGAUCUUUCUUUGGUCAGAGACCAGGGUUUGAGCCAAGGCUGUAAAUGUGAACAAUAGCUGUGCAAAGCCUUUUAACCUGACUUCUUCAUUUUGUAAAUUAUUAUGCAUUAAGUAGCAGCCCAAUAAUCUGAUUUCUAGUUUUAUUUUCAAAGUAAGUAGCUUCUUUUGGGAAAAACCUAAGUUAAACUAGUAGUUUUGCCAUAAUAACUGCUGAUUUAUGUAUUUGCUAAAGGUACUUUUGUAUCUGCUGUGUAUUAUAGCAAUAAAAUAAUCAUUUUGUUAGAAAAAAA